CUAAGUGUCUCCGCGGCGCACCUCGCGGCGAGAAUCCGGAGGAGAAGGAGACUGCAAGGAUAGGCCCAGGUCGGUGCGAGGGACGGUGGUGGGGCGGGGGUCGGAACGUAAGGAAAGCCCAGUCUGAGACCCCAACCCCCUCCACCCCAUCCCCCACUCCUAUACCGGUCCUCCAUUUUGGUGCCUGCAAAGCUCUGGGAAAGAAUCCCGGGAAACGAAAAAUGGUGGGUUUGGGGGAAGGGAGGUAAGGGGAGAAAGCUGGAGGGAGGGGCUUUAAUUGGAGGCCCCGUAGAGGACGCGCGGAACUUCUAAGGUGGGAAAAAACGAAAUUAAAAAAUCCUUUGAUAUCAGGGCUCUGAAUCCUGCUGGUCAGAGCACCAAGCAUUCAGUCUCUCUCCUUGCCUUUGUCUUACUUGUGUUCAAAGAAAAACAACCAGAAAAAAAAAAUCUCAUCAUGGCAAAUAUUCACCAGGAAAACGAAGAGAUGGAGCAGCCUAUGCAGAAUGGAGAGGAAGACCGCCCUUUGGGAGGAGGUGAAGGCCACCAGCCUGCAGGAAAUCGACGGGGACAGGCUCGCCGACUUGCCCCUAAUUUUCGAUGGGCCAUACCCAAUAGGCAGAUCAAUGAUGGGAUGGGUGGAGAUGGAGAUGAUAUGGAAAUAUUCAUGGAGGAGAUGAGAGAAAUCAGAAGAAAACUUAGGGAGCUGCAGUUGAGGAAUUGUCUGCGUAUCCUUAUGGGGGAGCUCUCUAAUCACCAUGACCAUCAUGAUGAAUUUUGCCUUAUGCCUUGACUCCUGCCAUUUAUCAUGAGAUUAAUACUGUGAUUCCCGCUGUUUUCUUUUUCCUUGCAUUUUCCUAAUAUGCCUUUACUGAUCCGUUUGCUGUGAACCCUAUGUUAUUUCCAUGUGUCAAGUGGGUCUUGUGUUGCCAGCUUCUAUUUGAAGAUUGCCUUUGCACUCAGUGUAAGUUUCUGUCAGCAGUAGUUUCACCCAUUUGCAUGGAAAAAUUUAAAGCUAAUAAAGCAAUUUAAAAAGCAAUCUAUACAUUUAUUGUCUCAUUAAAAAUGUAUACUUACAUAUAACAGAUGAACUAAAAAAAAAUCUGAGAUUAAAUACACUAGAGUGUUAA